GGUCCCUCGGACGAUUGGACCUAGCUUGGCGCGGAAUCCGUGAAUUGCCCGCGGCCCGAGGGUGCAGGUGAUGGGUGCUGACCGACUGGGGAAGCCCGGAGUGUGGGGACUGAGGAGGGGAGUGGCCUGGGGCGCGCUGGAGCCUGCGAGGAAGGCGCCGCCUCGGAUCCCCCGCCCCCCAUUCCCCUUCCCGAAUUCCACCCUCCGGCCCAGCCAUGGCCUCAGUUUCCCCAAACAGGAAAGGGAAGGAGGGUGGGCACCCCGGUCUAACGGUGCCUCUCAGCCUCUGAGACCCAGAACCUUCCUUCUGCAGCUCCCGGACUGACUGGCUCUGCCCUUCCCCAUGGACGCCUCCUCUAGCCCGUGGAAUCCAACCCCGGCUCCUGUCAGCAGCCCUCCCCUGCUGCUCCCCAUCCCUGCCAUCGUCUUCAUCGCUGUGGGCAUCUAUUUGUUGCUGCUGGGUCUAGUCCUGCUGACUAGGAACUGCCUGCUGGCCCAGGGCUGCUGCGCGGACGGUAGCUCCCCCUGCAGGAAGCAAGGUUCCUCCGGGCCCCCAGACUGCUGCUGGACCUGUGCAGAAGCCUGCAACUUUCCUCUGCCUAGCCCGGCCCACUUCCUGGAUGCUUGCUGCCCCCAGCCCACCAGAGCUGACUGGGCACCUCGCUGCCCCCGCUGCUGCCCACUCUGCGACUGUGCCUGUACGUGCCAGCUCCCCGACUGCCAGAGCCUCAACUGUCUCUGCUUCGAGAUCAAGCUCCGAUGAGGACCCAGGGCCCCUGCCCUCUGGGGAGCGGCCAGCCCCCAGGGCCCAUGUGCCCUCCUCCCUGAAGAGCCUUUCCCCACGCCACUGGAACCACAGAUGGCCUGCCGAGCACCCAGGCCUGGGAACUGGAAGUGGCAGCGCAGGGCCUGGCUCCCUGCAGGGCAGGACUCUUGGCCGGCUGGACGGCAGCUCCUCUGGAGGGCCAGAAAAGAGAGGGGCUAGUGCUCGGGCAGGUGCCCUGGCUUCCCUUCCCCUCCACACGUCAACGAUUCUAUUUGAAGUUGGGCAGGGGGGUGGCGCUGCUCACCACACACAAGUGUUAUAGGAGGAGUCUGGCCCUUGAGUACCGGGUACGCAGGGGUGCCUCAACCACACUCCGUCCACGGACUCUCCGUUAUUUUAGGAGGUCCCUGGCCAAAGAUUUAUUUCUCUUGACAACCAAGGGCCUCCGUCUGGAUUUCCAAGGAAGAAUUUCCUCUGAAGCACCGGAACUUGCUACUACCAGCACCAUGCCCUACCAAUAUCCAGCACUGACCCCGGAGCAGAAGAAGGAGCUGUCUGACAUCGCUCACCGCAUCGUGGCACCUGGCAAGGGCAUCCUGGCUGCAGAUGAGUCCACUGGGAGCAUUGCCAAGCGGCUGCAGUCCAUUGGCACCGAGAACACCGAGGAGAACCGGCGCUUCUACCGCCAGCUGCUGCUGACAGCUGACGACCGCGUGAACCCCUGCAUUGGGGGUGUCAUCCUCUUCCAUGAGACACUCUACCAGAAGGCGGAUGAUGGGCGUCCCUUCCCCCAAGUUAUCAAAUCCAAGGGCGGUGUUGUGGGCAUCAAGGUAGACAAGGGCGUGGUCCCCCUGGCAGGGACAAAUGGCGAGACUACCACCCAAGGGUUGGAUGGGCUGUCUGAGCGCUGUGCCCAGUACAAGAAGGACGGAGCUGACUUCGCCAAGUGGCGUUGUGUGCUGAAGAUUGGGGAACACACCCCCUCAGCCCUCGCCAUCAUGGAAAAUGCCAAUGUUCUGGCCCGUUAUGCCAGUAUCUGCCAGCAGAAUGGCAUUGUGCCCAUCGUGGAGCCUGAGAUCCUCCCUGAUGGGGACCAUGACUUGAAGCGCUGCCAGUAUGUGACCGAGAAGGUGCUGGCUGCUGUCUACAAGGCUCUGAGUGACCACCACAUCUACCUGGAAGGCACCUUGCUGAAGCCCAACAUGGUCACCCCAGGCCAUGCUUGCACUCAGAAGUUUUCUCAUGAGGAGAUUGCCAUGGCGACCGUCACAGCGCUGCGCCGCACAGUGCCCCCCGCUGUCACUGGGAUCACCUUCCUGUCUGGAGGCCAGAGUGAGGAGGAGGCGUCCAUCAACCUCAAUGCCAUUAACAAGUGCCCCCUGCUGAAGCCCUGGGCCCUGACCUUCUCCUACGGCCGAGCCCUGCAGGCCUCUGCCCUGAAGGCCUGGGGCGGGAAGAAGGAGAACCUGAAGGCUGCGCAGGAGGAGUAUGUCAAGCGAGCCCUGGCCAACAGCCUUGCCUGUCAAGGAAAGUACACUCCGAGCGGUCAGGCUGGGGCUGCUGCCAGCGAGUCCCUCUUCGUCUCUAACCACGCCUAUUAAGCGGAGGUGUUCCCAGGCUGCCCCCAACACUCCAGGCCCUGCCCCCUCCCACUCUUGAAGAGGAGGCCGCCUCCUCGGGGCUCCAGGCUGGCUUGCCCGCGCUCUUUCUUCCCUCGUGACAGUGGUGUGUGGUGUCGUCUGUGAAUGCUAAGUCCAUCACCCUUUCCGGCACACUGCCAAAUAAACAGCUAUUUAAGGGGGA